GCAGAGGGCGGGGAGGUGGGCAAGAUGGCGCUUGCCGAGUGAUUCUCCUCGAAUACCUCCUGCCGGCGCGGAGACACCGGGGCGGGGGUCCUGCCGCAACUACCUCCCUUCCUCCUCUCCCCCGCCCCCGGAGCCUUCAUCCUUCCCUUCCCCCCCCACCUCGAGGGGCGGGCCUGGUUCCCGGGACACCAUGUCGGACUCUGAGGAGGAGAGCCAGGACCGGCAACUGAAAAUCGUCGUGCUGGGGGACGGCGCCUCCGGGAAGACCUCCUUAACUACGUGUUUUGCUCAAGAAACUUUUGGGAAACAGUACAAACAAACUAUAGGACUGGAUUUCUUUUUGAGAAGGAUAACAUUGCCAGGAAACUUGAAUGUUACCCUUCAAAUUUGGGAUAUAGGAGGGCAGACAAUAGGAGGCAAAAUGUUGGAUAAAUAUAUCUAUGGAGCACAGGGAGUCCUCUUGGUAUAUGAUAUUACAAAUUAUCAAAGCUUUGAGAAUUUAGAAGAUUGGUAUACUGUGGUGAAGAAAGUGAGCGAGGAGUCAGAAACUCAGCCACUGGUUGCCUUGGUAGGCAAUAAAAUUGAUUUGGAGCAUAUGCGAACAAUAAAACCUGAAAAACACUUACGGUUUUGCCAGGAAAAUGGUUUUAGUAGCCACUUUGUCUCAGCCAAGACAGGAGACUCUGUCUUCCUGUGCUUUCAGAAAGUUGCUGCUGAAAUCCUUGGGAUCAAAUUAAACAAAGCAGAAAUAGAACAGUCACAGCGUAUUGUCAGGGCAGAAAUAGUGAAGUACCCGGAAGAAGAAAAUCAACAUACCACCUCUACUCAGAGUAGAAUCUGUUCAGUACAGUAGUGCAGAGGGUGGUGAAGGCAGAUAUUGUAAACUACAACCAGGAACCUAUGUCAAGGACUGUUAACCCUCCUAGAAGCUCUAUGUGUGCAGUUCAGUGAGCGCAUUUUUCUUUUGUGUUGAUAGUUCUGGCUGCCCUUCACCUCUGGGUGGGCCCGAGGACUUCUAGGAACUUGUUUUAUCAGUGACCAUCUCUGUAGUUCAGUUAACACUUUACUCCCAACUUGCUUCAUCAUUGCUAUUGCCUCACAGUGGCAGGCAGCUCCUUGGAUUUGAAAGAAUUCAACUUUGGGACCACACACUUUGAAUUCAAAAUGGAAAACCCAUUCCCUGGAAUUAGACUGCUUCAUUGCAAAAGAAUGAUGUUGUUUCUUUGUAUGUCCUUGCUUCUUUUUUCAUUGAUGUAAAUUUUUUUAACUUAAUAUGAAAACUCUCCAAGUCUUGAUCAUCAGCCAGGAUUUUGCCACAGCAAUUUCAUUCUCUUAUCGGAACUUGUAUGUGUCAAAGUAUACUUCAGAGUGCAAACAUUAAGCAAGUAAUAUAUUUUACCUACAGAUACUUAUGAAGACAUUCUUUCGCUAUCGUGAGUAAAAGUAUAUAAAGCUGUUUCUAACUGAAAAUGCUUGAAAUAAGCCUGUAAUAGAAAUAUUUUUUCAUUUUUUAAAAAAGGGCCUAAAUUGUUUAUAUUGUAGUUUGUAACUCACAAAGUAAUAUUUGAUAUUGUAUUUUUAUUACUGUAUCGUUGUCGUUAUGUAUUGUGUAAUACUCAGGUUUGAAGGCUUUCUGAAUUCUGAUAAAUGUUCAGCUGAUGCUCCACGUGGAAUUUCUCUUGCAAACUGCAUAAGAGUACUCCCGAGAAUGAGUUAUGACAUUGUGGAUCAGACUGUACCUGAUGUUCAGAUGUUUUUCUUUCACAAAUAAACUUAUUUAAAUUA